AGCCAAACUUCCGGCGGCGGCUGAGGCGGCGGCCGAGGAGCGGCGGACUCGGGGCGCGGGGAGUCGAGGCAUUUGCACCUGGGCUUCGGAGCGUAGCGCCAGGGCCUGAGCCUUUGAAGCAGGAGGAGGGGAGGAGAGAGUGGGGCUCCUCUAUCGGGACCCCCUCCCCAUGUGGAUCUGCCCAGGCGGCGGCGGCGGCGGCGGCGGAGGAGGAGGAGGAGGCGACCGAGAAGAUGCCCGCCCUGCGUCCCGCUCUGCUGUGGGCGCUGCUGGCGCUCUGGCUGUGCUGGGCGGCCCCCGCGCAUGCAUUGCAGUGUCGAGAUGGCUAUGAACCCUGUGUAAAUAAAGGAAUGUGUGUUACCUACCACAGUGGCACAGGAUACUGCAAAUGUCCAGAAGGCUUCUUGGGGGAAUAUUGUCAACAUCGAGACCCCUGUGAGAAGAACCGCUGCCAGAAUGGUGGGACUUGUGUGGCCCAGGCCAUGCUGGGGAAAGCCACGUGCCGGUGUGCCUCAGGGUUUACAGGAGAGGACUGCCAGUACUCGACACCUCAUCCAUGCUUUGUGUCUCGACCUUGCCUGAAUGGCGGCACAUGCCAUAUGCUCAGCCGGGAUACCUAUGAGUGCACCUGUCAAGUCGGGUUUACAGGUAAGGAGUGCCAAUGGACCGAUGCCUGCCUGUCUCAUCUCUGUGCAAAUGGAAGUACCUGUACCACUGUGGCCAACCAGUUCUCCUGCAAAUGCCUCACAGGCUUCACAGGGCAGAAGUGUGAGACUGAUGUCAAUGAGUGUGACAUUCCAGGACACUGCCAGCAUGGUGGCACCUGCCUCAACCUGCCUGGUUCCUACCAGUGCCAGUGCCUUCAGGGCUUCACAGGCCAGUACUGUGACAGACUGUAUGUGCCCUGUGCACACUCGCCUUGUGUCAAUGGAGGCACCUGUCGGCAGACUGGUGACUUCACUUUUGAGUGCAACUGCCUUCCAGAAACAGUGAGAAAUAAGAGGAACAGAGCUCUGGGAAAGAGACAGGCAAGUCUGGAAUGGAAAAGAACACGAUGAGAAUUAGACACUGGAAAAUAUGUAUGUGUGGUUAAUAAAGUGCUUUAAACUGAAUUGACAUUAACAGUAGGUGAUCAACUUUACUAUGUGCUUGUGCUUUUGCUUUUGAUGGAGUAAUUCAUUGUUUUCUUAUCCACCUAAAUGCACCCAGCUGCCCUUGAUUUUCUCUGGGCUACUGGCCUUCACAACCCUCUCCCAUGUACCCUCUCUGACUUUGGGGUAACCCUCCCCUAACUUAAAGCUAGAGAAUUCUGAAACUGAGGAGGGGAUCCUCUGUUAAUCAGUGAGCACUUUUUGAUGAGCUGAUAGAUGAUAUAUGAGAGACUAUGUGUGGCACAAUACUUUGUUACACUCUUCACUGAUACAAGUGUUGUAGAGUGCACACACAACCCAAAGAUAGAAAUAAAAAGAGGAGCAGUGUCGGGGAGCUUGGGGCCUGGUGUUCCAUGGAGAGGGAGAAAGGAACAAGCUUGGCCAAUUCAUUCAACUCCUUAUAAAAAUGAUGAGGAGGCUGAAAACCAAGAAUUUUGAUUGGGAACAGAAUACAAGCAGCUGAAGCAGAUGAAUUACUAAGCAACAAAGAUCCUGUUUUUAUACAAAUAUCCUUAGUACAAAAACAAAAGAAGGAAAACUGUAGGAGGGAGUAAUGUGCUAAGUAAGCAGAAUUGCCUCAAAAAGAAGUUGUUCUAGUUACUCUUUCAGAGUGGGAAUCUUAGAUUCUGGUAUUGUGGAUAUGGUUCACAUAUAAUGGGAUUGUGUGUUUUAUUUUGGAGGGAUUAAAGGUCAUAGUUUGGUCCUCAGUAUAAAAUCAACUGGUAAUUUAUUCAUUUCAUUUGGUAAAAAUGUAUUGACUGCCUGCUAUGUUCUAGGCACCAUGCUAUGUAUUUGGAAUACAGCUAUACAAAGCAUUGUCACAUAAUUGAAAUGAAAAUUUUAUAUUAUUUAAGUCACAAGAACAAGCUAUUUAAUUAUAUUACUUUUAGUUUCUCUUUUAAUAAAGAAUAGAUAAUGCUAUCAUUCUAGAUACUAAA